ACUGGAAGGGCCCUUAAACCAGAGCUAGUUCAGUUCUCUAACUUUACAUCCAAGGAUAUUGAAACUUAGGUUAACUUUGUUAUAUAUUUGUCUAUGUGAUCUUGAGCAAGUUGCUAAGCUUUUCUAGCCUCAGUUCCCAAUCUGUAAAAUGGAGAUGAUGACAACAUUAUCUACCCUUAAAUAAUUGUGAUGAUUAAACCAUAUGGGAUAAUGCAUGUCAUGUGCCUGAGAGAGAGAAAACACUUCAAAAUGGCGAGCUAAUAUUGUUUUUCUAUCAACAGGUAGUAAUUGGGCUUCUGCUGUGUAUCAAACUCUGCUCCAAAUAAUGAGGAUACAACAAGAAAUGAACACUGACCUUGUCUUCUUGAAGGCUGAGGGGGAAGACAGACAUAAAAACACAAACUCACAAACACUCUUGAUGGUGGUUGUGAUAAGCGGAGAGAUGGUGGCAGUGGUAGUGGGGAGCCGCUCCCCCAUCACUCACAUUACUGCCUGAGCUGCACCUCCUGUCAGAUCACUGGUGGCAUUAGAUUCCCAUAGGAGCACAAACCCUAUUGUGAACUGUGCAUGCGAGGGAUCGAGGUUGCACGCUUCUCAUGAGAAUCUAAUGCCUGAUGAUCCGUCGCUGUCUCCCAUCAUAUGCCAAUGGGAUUGUCUAAUUGCAGGAAAACAAGCUCAGGGCUCCCACUGAUUCUACAUUAUGGAUAGUGACAACCUCUGGUGGGACGCCUUUGCCACUGAAUUUUUUGAAGAUGACGCCACAUUAACCCUUUCAUUUUGUUUGGAAGAUGGACCAAAGCGAUACACUAUCGGCAGGACCCUCAUCCCCCGUUACUUUAGCACUGUGUUUGAAGGAGGGGUGACCGACCUGUAUUACAUUCUCAAACACUCGAAAGAGUCAUACCACAACUCAUCCAUCACGGUGGACUGCGACCAGUGUACCAUGGUCACCCAGCACGGGAAGCCCAUGUUUACCAAGGUAUGUACAGAAGGCAGACUGAUCUUGGAGUUCACCUUUGAUGAUCUCAUGAGAAUCAAAACAUGGCACUUUACCAUUAGACAAUACCGAGAGUUAGUCCCGAGAAGCAUCCUAGCCAUGCAUGCACAAGAUCCUCAGGUCCUGGAUCAGCUGUCCAAAAACAUCACCAGGAUGGGGCUAACAAACUUCACCCUCAACUACCUCAGGUUGUGUGUAAUAUUGGAGCCAAUGCAGGAACUGAUGUCGAGACAUAAAACUUACAACCUCAGUCCCCGAGACUGCCUGAAGACCUGCUUGUUUCAGAAGUGGCAGAGGAUGGUGGCUCCGCCAGCAGAACCCACAAGGCAACCAACAACCAAACGGAGAAAAAGGAAAAAUUCCACCAGCAGCACUUCCAACAGCAGCGCUGGGAACAAUGCAAACAGCACUGGCAGCAAGAAGAAGACCACAGCUGCAAACCUGAGUCUGUCCAGUCAGGUACCUGAUGUGAUGGUGGUAGGAGAGCCAACUCUGAUGGGAGGUGAGUUUGGGGACGAGGACGAAAGGCUAAUCACUAGAUUAGAAAACACGCAAUAUGAUGCGGCCAACGGCAUGGACGACGAGGAGGACUUCAACAAUUCACCCGCGCUGGGGAACAACAGCCCGUGGAACAGUAAACCUCCCGCCACUCAAGAGACCAAAUCAGAAAACCCCCCACCCCAGGCUUCCCAAUAAGAUGAUCGGCACCAGAAUCCACUGUCAAUAGGCCCGUGGGUGAUCAUUACAAUUGCAAAUCUUUACUUACAGGAGAGGAAACAGAAGAGAUAAAAACUUUUCCAUGCAAAUAUCUAUUUCUAAACCACAAUGAUCUGAUUUUCUUUCUUCUUUCUUUUUUUCUAAUUGAGAGGAUUAUUCCCAGUAAGCUUCCAUGACCCUUUCUUGGAGGCCUUCACAGGUAAUACAGAUACUGGCACUGAUUGUAAUUAAAAUGAGAGAAAACUCUAGCGCAUCUUCUGGCACGGUUUUAACAACGUGUUUGUGUUGAAUUUCCUUUUUAUGCAUCAAACGAAGGCCAUAUUGUCCAUAAAUGCUCAGUGCUCAGGAUCUCAUUAAUAUGCCGAACCUAACUACAGAUGACUUUUUAAUAUUGUAAAAUAUUUUCUGCUUUUUGACUUGCAUCUGAGAGUUUCUUGUUUCAGUAAAAAAAGAAAAGACAAAAAAAUCAGCUUUGGAAAGUAAUUUAAAUGUACCUUAUUUUUUUUUUCUUUAUGUUUUCUUUCAUUGGGCAACAGCUAAGAGGGCCCAGCAAGGUAAUUUAUGGUUGAGCUGAUGUCAAUUGGUUCUUGUCUUGAGUCGACUCAAUUUAGCCCAAGUGCUGAAACAAGAAAUGUCAUUUUUUUCAUCAAAGACACCAGGGCAGAUUUUUAAGUAAAGAAAGACAAUUGGACCCUUAAGAAUUUAUGCAUUUGUAAAGUUGCUGUUGAUCCAAAUAUUUUCAAGCCAUGUAAUCCAUUGGUUUUGUGGGCAGUUUAAUAAACCUGAACCUUUGUGUGUUUUCUAAUUGUACCUGAGUUGACCAUCCUUUCUUUUUAUAGUAUAUUUCUUGUAUGAUAUUUUGUAAAGCUCUCACCUGGUUCUUUUAUGGGGACUUUUCGUUUUUGGGCAACUCCAGUGUAUUUAUGUGAAACUUUAUAAGAGAAUUAAUUUUUCCAUUUGCAUAUUAAUAUGUUCCUCCACACAUGUAAAGGCACAGUGGCUCCGUGUGUUAAAAAACAGCUGUAUUUUAUGUAUGCUUUACUGAUAAGUGUGCCAAUAAUAAACUGUGUUAAUGACCAAA